GAAAGACGCCCCGAUCCGGACGCUGGUGCAGCGCAUCCACCAGCUGCAGGCUGAGCGCGCGCAGGGCUUCCGCCGACUGGAGGAGUGAGUGGGGGCGCGGAGGGGCUCAGGGUUCGGUCCCCCGCCCGCUCCGGGCGUGGGCGUGUUCUCGGCGGGCGUGCCUGGAGGAGGAGCUGGGUCCUUGUGUGGCUGCAGAGUCAGAUGGGGCGGGGAUUUCGGGGCACCGGGUCCUCACCUUCACGAAAAAGGCCCCACAGCACGUCCCCACUACCCGACGACUCACUCUUCGUGGCUUCUCUCUCCUCCCCAAGAGCAGGGGUGGGCCUGUCUCGCGUUCCCCUGCGGGAGUCAGGAAGCGUCCUUCCUACCUACCAGUCCUCCCCUCUGGUGUCUGGGGACACUUCCUGGGGGCCUUUCAGGUGGUUGGCGCCGGUGCAGGGCCUGAGAGCCUGGGGGCGCGGCCUCAGGGUCCCCACAUGCCGCAGAGGCCACCGCCAGUACCUGCGCAGCGGCCCUGACUACGACUUCGCGCGCUACCGGAGCACAGUGCACGGGGUGACCCAGGCCUUCGCCGCCGCCUCGCGGGAGGUGCUGGCGGUGGAAGCAGAGCUGGGCGGGCCUCGCAGGCAGCCGCUGCUCGCCGGCCACGUGCGCAGCCUGCAGGAGCUGGAGCAGACGCGGCUGGGCACGGUGGCCCUGCUGCAGUUGAUGGAGACGCCAGAGCUGGCGGGGCAGGAGGACGCUGUACGGAUGCAGCAGCUGAAAAUGAAGGUAAUUAAAACCAUGGAGGCGAUCAGCGAGGUUCUCCAGGACCUUAGGUUUGAUGCGGAAUCUGCCGAGUGAUGGCGGCUCCCCAGGGAUGCGCCGAGGGAGAUGGGAAACGGGGCGGAUGGCGCCCAGCCCAGCCCUAACUGCCAGCUGGCUGGGGUUGCGCCCCACUGCGCUGCUGACCUUCCUGCAGUUCCAGACACCUCCCACAAUAAAGAGCUCCUCCUCUGUA